UGGACGGGGCCUGAGCUACAACUUCACCCACCUGGACGGGUACCUGGACCUUCUCAGGGAGAACCAGCUCCUCCCAGGUGAGCUGUGGGCUCUGCCCUCCCAGCCCGCCUGCACCCCCUUGCCCUGCCCACCCUCUCCCUCACCCAGCCCCUCUGAGUCCUUGGAUGUCCAUUCAGGGCUGGCCUUGGUGCCGGAGCACAGGCCUGGCAGAGCAUGGGUGUGGUGUGUGGUGGGCGGUGGGGCAGCCCUCCUGUGUUCCAGGGUUUGAGCUGAUGGGCAGCGCCUCGGGCCACUUCACUGACUUUGAGGACAAGCAGCAGGUGUUUGAGUGGAAGGACUUGGUCUCCAGCCUGGCCAGGAGAUACAUCGGUGGGCGAGCGCAGGCCCUGGGGCCCUGGCCGGGGCGGGGGUACUCCUGGGCAGGUUGCACCCCUAUCACGCAGGCUGCUGCCUGGUCAGGAGAUACAUUGGUGGGCAGGCGCAGGCCCUUGUGGGGGGAUGGGGGUGACAAGGGAUAGGUUGGUGGUCGGCGCAGGCCCUGGGGCCCCAGGCUGGGGGGUACUCCUGGGCUUGGUGGGUGGGCGAAGGCCCUGGGCCCCUGGGGUGGGGGGUACUCCUGGGCAGGCUGCACCCCUAUCACCCAGGCCGCACCCCUAUCACCCAGGCCGCCGCCCAGGUCUUGGACCCCCUUGAGCCAGCGCUUCCUGAUGUGGGGCGGGAGGCUGGCCUGCAUGGAGAUGGGGUUCAUCUUGAGUCAGACGCCCUUCAUCACCUUGCACCCUCCCUCCGUGGGAGUCACUGAGGCGAGAUUCACCUGUGCUGGGGGGACAGCAAGGCUCCUCUGCAGGUAGGUACGGACUGGCGCAUGUUUCCAAGUGGAACUUCGAGACGUGGAAUGAGCCAGACCACCACGACUUUGACAACGUCUCCAUGACCAUGCAAGGUGUAGACGCAGUGCUCCCCCGGCCCAGGCUUCCUGAACUACUACGAUGCCUGCUCGGAGGGUCUGCGCGCCGCCAGCCCCGCCCUGCGGCUGGGAGGCCCCGGCGACUCCUUCCACACCCCACCGCGAUCCCCGCUGAGCUGGGGCCUCCUGCGCCACUGCCACGACGGUACCAACUUCUUCACUGGGGAGGCGGGCGUGCGGCUGGACUACAUCUCCCUCCACAGGAAGGGUGCGCGCAGCUCCAUCUCCAUCCUGGAGCAGGAGAAGGUCGUCGCGCAGCAGAUCCGGCAGCUCUUCCCCAAGUUCGCGGACACCCCCAUUUACAACGACGAGGCGGACCCGCUGGUGGGCUGGUCCCUGCCACAGCCGUGGAGGGCGGACGUGACCUACGCGGCCAUGGUGGUGAAGGUCAUCGCGCAGCAUCAGAACCUGCUACUGGCCAACACCACCUCCGCCUUCCCCUACGCGCUCCUGAGCAACGACAAUGCCUUCCUGAGCUACCACCCGCACCCCUUCGCGCAGCGCACGCUCACCGCGCGCUUCCAGGUCAACAACACCCGCCCGCCGCACGUGCAGCUGUUGCGCAAGCCGGUGCUCACGGCCAUGGGGCUGCUGGCGCUGCUGGAUGAGGAGCAGCUCUGGGCCGAAGUGUCGCAGGCCGGGACCGUCCUGGACAGCAACCACACGGUGGGCGUCCUGGCCAGCGCCCACCGCCCCCAGGGCCCGGCCGACGCCUGGCGCGCCGCGGUGCUGAUCUACGCGAGCGACGACACCCGCGCCCACCCCAACCGCAGCGUCGCGGUGACCCUGCGGCUGCGCGGGGUGCCCCCCGGCCCGGGCCUGGUCUACGUCACGCGCUACCUGGACAACGGGCUCUGCAGCCCCGACGGCGAGUGGCGGCGCCUGGGCCGGCCCGUCUUCCCCACGGCAGAGCAGUUCCGGCGCAUGCGCGCGGCUGAGGACCCGGUGGCCGCGGCGCCCCGCCCCUUACCCGCCGGCGGCCGCCUGACCCUGCGCCCCGCGCUGCGGCUGCCGUCGCUUUUGCUGGUGCACGUGUGUGCGCGCCCCGAGAAGCCGCCCGGGCAGGUCACGCGGCUCCGCGCCCUGCCCCUGACCCAAGGGCAGCUGGUUCUGGUCUGGUCGGAUGAACACGUGGGCUCCAAGUGCCUGUGGACAUACGAGAUCCAGUUCUCUCAGGACGGUAAGGCGUACACCCCGGUCAGCAGGAAGCCAUCGACCUUCAACCUCUUUGUGUUCAGCCCAGACACAGGUGCUGUCUCUGGCUCCUACCGAGUUCGAGCCCUGGACUACUGGGCCCGACCAGGCCCCUUCUCGGACCCUGUGCCGUACCUGGAGGUCCCUGUGCCAAGAGGGCCCCCAUCCCCGGGCAAUCCAUGAGCCUGUGCUGAGCCCCAGUGGGUUGCACCUCCACCGGCAGUCAGCGAGCUGGGGCUGCACUGUGCCCAUGCUGCCCUCCCAUCACCCCCUUUGCAAUAUAUUUUUAUAUUUUAUUAUUUUCUUUUAUAUCUUGGUACCAACGCCCCCUUUAAAGCGGCUUUGCACAGGUCAGUCUCGGGUUGAGGCUCUGUGGCUUGGCCCUGGGCACAUUCCAGGGCAGCCUCCAAGGGUAAACCCCGGUGGCUGAUGAGGACCCAGCUGGAGCGAGGCCUCUUUCCCCCUCGCUCCCACUCAGACCACCCCCAAGCCUGGACUGGAAGUGUGUUGAGCCCCUGGGUCAGGCUGGCGAGCCAGCUCGGCCCUGCCCACCCAGGGGUUUCCGAGAUCACCCCUGGUGAGGCGGCGUGCCAGUCCCUUGCUUUCUUACUUGUUCUGCAGAGCGGGGAGCUGAGGCUGCAUGAGGGAAGACUCCCGUACCCCAGCACGGUGGAGGGUGGGAUGGGGUCACGCCUGUGCGACCCAGGAGGUGGCCAGCAGAAGGAAACAGUAGUGUCCACCAUGGUCUGCGUCUCCCCACCACGGAUUGUCUUGGCUCCGGAUUUGAGACAUGGCAGGGCCAGAUGAGGACAACUUGAUGACAGUUUACAGAGAUGGAGGCAGGGUGCCAGGAAGCCACGGGGGAGCCCCCAGGGCACUCAGCAGUCCAGGCAGGGCUGGGCGUCCUGGCAAGGAGCAGGGACCUUCUGCCCAGGGGUGUGGCCAGCCUGUGGGUGCUGUGUGCAGGACCCCAGGAACCAAGGCCGCAGUCUCUUCCCUCGCUCCAGCAUCCUCCCAAGGCCACCCUUGGCUGCACUCAGCCAGAGAGCUGGGGCACAGGGACCCCACAGGUUUCCCUGGAGGCUGUCAGGGGCUCCGGUGGGGGCGGGGGGUGAGCCCGCUGGGUUCACUGCACCUCCCAAAGCCCAUGUGCCCUGCCUGCCCCAACCAAAGUGGGCCUCCAAGGUGCUGGGGUGGGACAGAGACCCACGAGGGACCCUCCCCUCACUCCUGGACCUGGGUGUUGUGGCUUUUGGCAAAAAUAGCCACAUACACUCCAAGUUUCCCCCUCAGCUGGGAUUCCUGGUGUGAGCCUGGUCACCAGGGUGGUAGGACAGACCCUCCUCUGGAGGCAAAGUGACGGUCAGCAGGGGGUUCUGAGGCCCCACAGCGCUGGCACCAGUCUUGGCUGAAUGGCAAAGCUGCAUCUGUCUCCUUCCCCAUGAGCUUCCGUUGCCGUCUCCUUCCCUGGCGGCCAUCAGCUUACUGACGUGUCCUCACCAGCUUACUGACGCGUCCCCACCCUCCGGUCUUGCUCCUGGGGUCACUUUGGCCUUCGCUGUGAAUGGGUCAGGCUUGAGGCCAUGCCAAGAGCCAGGGAAGCCAGCACUGGCCGUCAGCUCACACACAGCCUCUGAGAUGGAGUCUCGCUCUGUCACCCAGGCUGGAGUGCAGUGGCGUGAUCUCGGCUCACUGGAAGCUCCGCCUCCCAGGUUCACGCCAUUCUCCUGCCUCAGCCUCCUGAGUAGCUGGGAAUACAGGCGCCCACCACCACACCCGCAUCUUGAACAUAUGGAACAUGGUCACAGCAUAAGCAUGUGUGUGCUGUCCUCUACUUGCCCUGUCACCUCCAGCAUCUUGAACAUAUGGAACAUGGUCACAGCAUAAGCAUGUGUGUGCUGUCCUCUACUUGCCCUGUCACCUCCAGCAUCUUGAACAUAUGGAACAUGGUCACAGCAUAAGCAUGUGUGUGCUGUCCUCUACUUGCCCUGUCACCUCCAGCAUCUUGAACAUAUGGAACAUGGUCACAGCAUAAGCAUGUGUGUGCUCUCCUCUACUUGCCCUGUCACCUUUGUCAUUUCCAGGUCAGUUACUACAACCUCCACCUCCCGGAUUCAAGUGAUUCUCCUGCCUCAGCCUUCUGAGUAACUGGGGCUACAGGUUGCCUGCCACCACGCCUGGCUAGUUUUUUUAUUUUUAGUAGAGAUGGGGUUUCACCAUGUUGUCCAGGCUGGUUGUGAACUUCUGGUCUGAAGUGAUUCGCCCUCCUCGGCCUCCCAGAGUGCUGGGAUUACAGGCGUGAGCCACUGUGCCCGGCCCCAGGUCAAUUUUGAUUGAUUUUUCCCAUCUCUCCAUAUGGGUCAUAAUGUCCUGCCUCUUUUCAUGCCUGUUUUUUUGUUUUUUGUUUUUCCCGGAUAUUCAAUAUUUUGUAUUCUACCUUGUUUGGUGCUGGAUAUUUUUGUAAACCUAUACAUAUCUUUGCAUUUGUUUCUCGAAUGUGAUCAAGUUACUUGGAAA